CCCCUGCCUCACACUGGCCUCUCUCACGCUGAGGGAGGUCAGCGUGGGCCCCUGCCUCACACUGGCCUCUCUCACGCUGAGGGAGGUCAGCGUGGGCCCCUGCCUCAAACUGGCCUCUCUCACGCUGAGGGAGGUCAGCGUGAGGCCCUGCCUCACACUGGCCUCUCUCACGCUGAGGGAGGUCAGCGUGAGGCCCUGCCUCACACUGGCCUCUCUCACGCUGAGAGAAGUCCUCCCUCACGCUGGCCUGUUGAGGCCCAGUUCAUGCCUCUGUUGGCUUCUCCAGGCCCAGCCCCUGCCUGUUGGCGGCCUCUACCUCAACAGUGGGCCCUCCACGCCCACCUCUUGCCUCGCCGUGGCCUCCUCGGGCCAGGCUCCCGCCUUGGGGCAGCUCCCGCAGGCCCAGCUCCUGCCUCACGGCCCUCCGGAGGCCAAGCUCAUGUGUCAGGGCGGCCUCUCCCGGCCUGGCGUUUGCUCCUUUGCAUGGGCUCCAAAUCCUGCACUUCCUCCAGUCGUUCUCUCCAGGCCCAGCUCUUCCUCCCAGCAGCCUCUGCAGGACCAGACUGUCGUCAAGUAGGCCUGUCCAGGGACAGCUCCUGCCUCCCGGCAGACUCUGCAGGCCCAAGUCGUCCUCAAGUCAGCCUCCCCAGGCCCAGCUCCGGCCUCUCGGCGGCCUCUCCAGGUGCAAAAGUUCCUCGAGUCCGUCUCUCCAGGUCCAGCUCCUCCUGUCUCCCAGUGGCCUCUUUCAGCCCAGCCCAGCUCAUGCCUCCCGGCGGCCUUCCCAGGCCCCGCUUCUGACUUUCCGCGGCCUCUGCAGGCCCCGAACUUGACCUCCAGUCGGCCUCUGCAGGCCUGGCCUCCUGCCUCCCGAAAGCUUGCACAGGCCCAGCCUCUGCCUCACAGCGGACUCUCCACGCCCAGCUCGCUCUCGCCUGCGGCCUCCCGAGUCCAAAG